AACAGUUCCCCAGGGACCUCUCUCUAAUCAGCCCUCUGGCCCAGGCAGUCAGAUCAUCUUCUCGAACCCCGAGUGACAAGCCUGUAGCCCAUGUUGUAGCAAACCCUCAAGCUGAGGGGCAGCUCCAGUGGCUGAACCGCCGGGCCAAUGCCCUCCUGGCCAAUGGCGUGGAGCUGAGAGAUAACCAGCUGGUGGUGCCAUCAGAGGGCCUGUACCUCAUCUACUCCCAGGUCCUCUUCAAGGGCCAAGGCUGCCCCUCCACCCAUGUGCUCCUCACCCACACCAUCAGCCGCAUCGCCGUCUCCUACCAGACCAAGGUCAACCUCCUCUCUGCCAUCAAGAGCCCCUGCCAGAGGGAGACCCCAGAGGGGGCUGAGGCCAAGCCCUGGUAUGAGCCCAUCUAUCUGGGAGGGGUCUUCCAGCUGGAGAAGGGUGACCGACUCAGCGCUGAGAUCAAUCGGCCCGACUAUCUCGACUUUGCCGAGUCUGGGCAGGUCUACUUUGGGAUCAUUGCCCUGUGAGGAGGACGAACAUCCAACCUUCCCAAACGCCUCCCCUGCCCCAAUCCCUUUAUUACCCCCUCCUUCAGACACCCUCAACCUCUUCUGGCUCAAAAAGAGAAUUGGGGGCUUAGGGUCGGAACCCAAGCUUAGAACUUUAAGCAACAAGACCACCACUUCGAAACCUGGGAUUCAGGAAUGUGUGGCCUGCACAGUGAAGUGCUGGCAACCACUAAGAAUUCAAACUGGGGCCUCCAGAACUCACUGGGGCCUACAGCUUUGAUCCCUGACAUCUGGAAUCUGGAGACCAGGGAGCCUUUGGUUCUGGCCAGAAUGCUGCAGGACUUGAGAAGACCUCACCUAGAAAUUGACACAAGUGGACCUUAGGCCUUCCUCUCUCCAGAUGUUUCCAGACUUCCUUGAGACACGGAGCCCAGCCCUCCCCAUGGAGCCAGCUCCCUCUAUUUAUGUUUGCACUUGUGAUUAUUUAUUAUUUAUUUAUUAUUUAUUUAUUUACAGAUGAAUGUAUUUAUUUGGGAGACCGGGGUAUCCUGGGGGACCCAAUGUAGGAGCUGCCUUGGCUCAGACAUGUUUUCCGUGAAAACGGAGCUGAACAAUAGGCUGUUCCCAUGUAGCCCCCUGGCCUCUGUGCCUUCUUUUGAUUAUGUUUUUUAAAAUAUUUAUCUGAUUAAGUUGUCUAAACAAUGCUGAUUUGGUGACCAACUGUCACUCAUUGCUGAGCCUCUGCUCCCCAGGGGAGUUGUGUCUGUAAUCGCCCUACUAUUCAGUGGCGAGAAAUAAAGUUUGCUUAGAAAAGAAA